CUGCGCACGCGCGGCCGCUCCUGCGGGCGGAAGCCUCCUGGCGCUCGGCCCUGCGCCCCUCCCCCCGGCGCGCGGCCCCGCCCAGGACGAGGGGCGGUGGGCAGGCAGCGCUGGGUCCAGUGGUCGGGGGAAGGCGAGGAUUACCCUCCCGGAGGCGUUGUCUGCGACUCGGCGGAGGCUCCAACUUCCAGUGGCCCGGUCGGGAAAGAUCUGCCUCUUUCUGUACCACCCAGAUCAGAGCCUCCUAAGAAAUAUCCAGAAGUCAAGCCAUGGAUCCACCUGCACGUAAAGAAAAAACCAAAGUUAAAGAAUCUGUCAGCAGAGUUGAGAAGGCCAAACAGAAAUCAGCCCAGCAGGAGCUGAAGCAGAGACAAAGAGCAGAGAUCUAUGCCCUCAACAGAGUCAUGACAGAACUGGAGCAGCAGCAGUUUGAUGAGUUCUGUAAACAGAUGCAGCCUCCUGGAGAAUGAGGCCCCAGGUUCAAACCAGAUGGGAUCCUGAGAGCUUUGAGAGGGUGUUGCCAGUUUUAAGCUGAGAUGGCCCAUUUGGAGCCUUACAGAACUAGACCAGAAGACAUUUGUGGAUAAAUCUGAACUCACUUCCUGUGUGUAACUUCUAACUUCACUGGUUCCUCCCAUCUGAAUUGGCCACAUGCUUGCUGAAGAGACUUGUUUUCUUCUUCUAAGACAGUGGUUUUGUUUUUUGGGUUUUUUUAAAAAAAAAAAAAAAACACACACAAAAAACACUUUUUCUAUUGUUUGAGAAAAAUCAGUGUUUCUCAUGAAACUCUAUAUCUUCUCCAAAAAUACAAAUAAAAUACUAAUAAAAUGUU